CUCUCGAGUCCGGGCCGCAAGUCCCAGACGCUGCCCAUGGAGGCGUCCAGCGAGCCGCCGCUGGAUGCUAAGUCCGAUGUCACCAACCAGGUGGGUGAGCGGCCGCCCCGCCCUGUCCUCCGCCAGCCUGCCUCCCACGGCCGCGAGGCCGUGCCACCCUGAGCCUUCCCCAGGUCUCCCCUAGUCCUGUGUCCGCGAGCCGGUGACCUUCAGCCGUCCCUCUUGCAUUGCUCCUUCUCUUUUGCACCUGAGCCGGUAGCCGUUGCCAUUCUUGUAGAUUUUCAGUGGAAACUGGGUAUGGCUGUGAGCUCAGACACUUGCAGAUCUCUUAAGUAUCCUUACGUUGCAGUGAUGCUAAAAGUGGCAGAUCAUUCAGGCCAAGUAAAGACCAAGUGCUUUGAAAUGACGAUUCCACAGUUUCAGAAUUUCUACAGACAGUUCAAGGAAAUUGCUGCAGUUAUUGAAACGGUGUGAAGACGGAUUCUUUGGUUGAUAAAUUGCUAUCAUUCUAAAGUCAUGGACUUCACUUUCGGCAACAAAACUAAAUAAGGAUGGAACAUUUAUUGAAUGAAAAAUGCACUUUUGUUUUUCCAUUUUUUUAAAUAAUAAAAAUCAGACAAACAGGAACUGGGUAGUGGUGAUGAAUGCAAAACUUUGUGAAUGUGCUUUAUAAAAGUGAUAAUUAGACACUUUAGAGGAUAUACUUGGUGAUAAUGUGAAUGAUGUAAUCAGACUAACAGUUGAAUCAUUGCUGUUGGAGGCAGCACAAAUUUAUGUGUUACAACAGUAGUUUAAAAACUUGUACUGGAUGGAACCCAUUUUAUAAACAGUCUUAUUUGGAGUCAUGUAUAUAAAAAUAUAUAUAAAUUAGAAAAGUAGUAUUUGAUUAGGAUAACUUUACAAAUUCAAUAGUAUAGCCAUCACUUAUUAUAAUGGCAAUCAGAAGAGUGAGGCUUCUUUUUUCAAACUUUUGUAAUCAGAUUAAGAUUGACCAUUGCUCCUUUACACAGUAUUAGUCUAGCAUUCAAUUAUUUCUGUUAUUAAUGGUUGUAGAAAGUUCAAAUACAUACGCAGAGUUGGAAAGACGAGUUUUAGUCUGAGUUCUGUACGACGGAGUUAACCCGUUAGCACAAGUUAUUGCAUUAGAUGAUCUCUGUUGAAUUUAAAUACAUAAACCUGUUGUUAAACGCUUUUAUACUAUAAAGCCACCACAUUGUAUGGCAUUUGUUUAGAAGUAAGCAAAUAGACCACCGGAAUAGAAUAGAUGGCCUAGAAAUAGAUCAAGACAUUCUGGUCCGCCAUAUUAGAAAUUUAAACCCUCUUCACACCCUGUCUGCAUUUCUGCAGGUCUGUGUGAGUCCACUUUCUUUUUUGUUCCCUGCUAGGUAGCACACAGCUGUGAGGAGCCCAGGACUGCUGCCUGCCGCAGCCCACCUGUGCGCUCAGAUUCCUACCAGCUUGAUGAGUUAGCUGAUGGGCCAUUUGUGCAUACCAACUACCCACAGACAUUUCUAUUACCCACCCUCUGGAUGCCAGUGCAUUAAUGAUUCUAGAAUUAGGAGAAACCAAAGAUCCCUUCUCUCUCCCUCCCACAACCAGUGUCGUCGUGUUCCUAGAAAUAAGAGUAGAAACCCCUCUAUCUGGGUUAAAACAGCAAACCUGCCUUCUGUAACUGUGCAUGAGGUUCCUCUGUCUCCCACUUACUUCGGAUUAACACCUUCCUCUUUCCCCUUCCCUGUUUGCAGGGUAGCAUUUCUAGGUUUAAGGCAAUAUGCAAAAAGACCCAAAGUUAGGCCCUGGCUCAAACACUGUGGGUAGCAGAUUUGAAAUAAAUUUAAAUUGCAUGUUU